AGAAGCCAGCUGAGAGCGCCUGCGCGGCUGUCGGUUGAUGGGGAGGUCAGGUCUGGGAAACUAGGCCCUGGGGUUUUCCCUGAGCAGGAGCGGUGCCCGAGGGCCUCAGGUACGCAGAAGGGCGGGGAGACAUGGGAUCAGCACCUCCACCUCCUAAGGGACCGAAGGGCAGGAGAGCGAGAGGACUUGUCCCCAGAGGUGGAGUCCGAAGUGGGGGCGCCCCAGUUGACCCUUCGGGACAAAACGUGACUUCAGCCUUAAGGAUCUAAAACCGGCCGCGGUCAGGUCAGGUGGCCCUCAACGCUCAGGCGUCAGUCCAGGCCCUGAAUGGCUGGUCUCCAGCGGUUGGCGUCACAUCUGCCUGUGGGCGUUAUGCUCCCACAUAAUACAACGGAAGCUCCAGGGCCCCACUCAGCCAAGCAAGACUCUUACGAACAAGGUGACUCUUCCCAGCAGUCCUUGAAGGGGCACCUGAGGAACAAUUUCCAGAAGCAGCUUUUGAGCAACAAAGAGUUGAUUCUGGAUAAAGUCUAUACUCACCCCAAAUGGAACACCCAAACAAAAGCCCGGAGCUACUCCUAUCCCCACUGUACUGGAAUCAGCCAGCAAGAUCCAGAAAGUGAUUCCCAGGGCCAAGGAAAUGGUUUGUUUUACUCGUCAGGCCCUCAAUCCUGGUAUCCCAAAGCCAAUAACCAGGACUUUAUCCCCUUUACAAAGAAACGAGUUGGAGUGGACCGGGCGUUCCCAUUGAAACCCAUGGUCCACAGGAAGUCGUGCAGUACAGGUGAGGCUGGCACUGAUGGGGACCAUAAUGUCUACCCAAGGCCCCCUGAGCCGAGAGAGUUUUCAUCUAGGAACUUUGGUGUGAGGAACCAGGGCAACUUUUCUGUGGUUGGUACUGUUCUUGCUGCCACGCAGGCGGAGAAGGCCGUGGCAAACUUUGACAGGACGGAGUGGGUGCAGAUCCGAAGACUAGAAGCUGCAGGGGAGAGCUUAGAGGAGGAAAUCCGAAGAAAGCAGAUUCUCCUGAGGGGAAAGCUGAAGAAGACAGAGGAGGAACUCAGAAGGAUCCAGACGCAAAAGGAACAGGCCAAGGAAAAUGAAAACGGAGAGCUACAGAAAAUUAUACUCCCCAGGAGCAGAGUUAAAGGUAAUAAAAGCAACACCAUGUACAAACCUAUCUUCUCCCCAGAAUUUGAGUUUGAGGAAGAAUUUAGUAGAGACAGGAGAGAGGAUGAAACUUGGGGACGGUCUCAACAAAAUUCAGGUCCAUUCCAGUUCUCUGAUUAUAGAAUCCAGAGGCUCAAAAGGGAAAGGCUGGUAGCAAGCAAUAAUAAAAUUCGAGACCCAGUCUCAGAGCCAUCGGUGGAGAAAUUCUCCCCGCCUUCAGAAACACCAGUCGGUGCUUUGCAGGGAUCCGCCAGAAAUUCCAGCCUGUCCAUGGCACCAGACUCCUCAGGUUCCAGCGGCUCCAUUGAAGAGCCACAGCUGGGUGAGUGCAGCCACUGUGGGCGCAAAUUCCUCUCGUUCAGGCUGGAGAGACACUCCAACAUCUGCAGCAGGAUGCGGGGUUCCAAGAGGAAAGUGUUUGACUCCUCCAGGGCCCGGGCUAAGGGCACAGAACUAGAGCAGUACUUGAACUGGAAGGGGCCAGCUUCAGCCAAGGCUGAACCUCCUCAGAAGAGCAACUGGAGAUAGAAGCAUGAAUCUUUUAUCCAUACGUUCCGCCAGGCUCGAGAGGUCCAGCAGGUAACUGCCAAAGGUGGAAACUGUUCACACUUGCCUCCCAUCCUGCCUGCAGAAAACCCAGACUGCAUUCAGUGUCCUCAGUGUAGCCACCACUUUGCUCCCAAGGUGGCUGAGCAACACAUUCCCAAGUGUAAGACCAUCAAGAACUGUCUUCCACCUCUAAGGAAGCAUUAUAGUUGAGCAGACAACAAUGGAAACUUUUGGAUAGUUCAGAAAGCUCUGCUUCUCUUCAGCAGUAAAUGGGAGUAGAAUUUGAUGCAAAGCAGAAAGAAAUCAAACAGCUCCCAGAUCUGCCUGCAGAGCUAAAAUCUGUGAGGAGAGAGCCACUGCUAAGCAGCAGGAGGCAGAAGGAAGCCCCAGCUUCCCACUAAAUUACAACCUUGGGCUGGUAUGCUUUAUGUUAUUGCCCUCAGAAUUGAUGGGUGAAGACACUGAAGAGUCAUGAGCAGGCUCCAUUAAAGCUCUUUUCUUGCAUGCCUGACUUGUGGUUUGUGCUAGUUAAGUGCCUGCAUCUGGUUCUGCCUUCUUGUCACUGCAUGUAUGUUCAGAGUUCCUGUUAACUCUUGCUUUUGUAGAAGCUGGAGUUAUUAGGAUGUGUUGGUGUCAGAGGGGCAUGAUCACCCAGAUAGUAACUCUUAUAAAAGAUAAUACAAUUUUGCUAUAAGGCAUUAUUAAUGGAAAUCUAUCCUUGGUCUCCCUGGUGCAUAAGCCUGGCCAAAACCCAAUACAAGUAUGUAAGGUUAAGGCACCAAUGUCUCCUAAACCUUCCCUAUGGUGUACUGUGUAAUAAAGGAAAGAUCUUUAUGUACUUUACAGGGUAGGGAUGGGUGUUGGGGGGGAAACACAUUAUACUUCUCUCUACUUGUUCUUUUCUAAUGGGUUUCAUAUGUUAAGAAAGAAACCUCCAUUUUAGCUGUUAGUAGCACUCUACUUUCAAAUCGGUUUGGCUAAAUGACUGUUUAGAGGCAGCAAAAUCUACCAUCAAAGCAAGCUGAGACAGGCUGGUCAUGGUGGCUCAUUCCUAUAAUUCCAGCACUUUGGGAGGCUGAAGUGGGAGGAUUGCUUGAGGCCAGGAGUUCAAGAGCGGCCUCGACAACAAAGCAAGACCCCAUCUCAAAACAAAACAAAGCUGGGACACUGCACAGUGUCACAUGCCCUUGGCAAUUAUAGCAUAGUCAACUUCUAUUUCAGAGAGUAAACUUUGAAGGGAAAGGGAUCAAAUCUUUUUAAUUUUCUCUGUGUAGAAUAUUGCCUAGCACAAGUUAGACCUUCAAUUAGUGAGGUCUGGAGAUUUAAAAUUAAACAAGAAGAUGAGUGAGUCCUACACUAGUGAAAUCAGAGAACUGAUAAGUUAAUGUCUGCGAGAGUAUUAUCAGUUCAGAUAGGAGUGAAGUUAGCACAACAGAUAGAAAUCUUAGGAUUACUGUUCUGUAUUACUCAAAUUGUUAGUUUAAAAUACUGGAGAAAAACUGCUCAAUUUGAGCUAGUCAACAGGGCUAGACAGACAACAAAAUCCUAUUUUACUAAGUAACAAAUGGCCACUCACUCUUGCUCCAUUUCCACUGCACUCCAGCCUGGUGACCUAGUGAGACUCCAUCUCAAAAAAAAAAAAAAAAAAAAGAAAAAAAAAUUGGGCUAACAGAUCAGACCAAUUUGAAAUGUGAGUUAAGGCUUUAGCGGUGAAGCUGCAGGACACAGGCUGGGAAAAAAUCCUAUAUAUUUAAAUAGGAGCACACAUUUCUUUGCACUCUUUUUAAUUGUUCCAAAGGAAAGGAGGUAUCACAUAAUAAAGCUUUAUGGUUAGCCCCUUAAGGAAACCUCACACAGAGAUAAUGGAUAUUUAACCUAAUAGGUACAUUCCCUAGGCAAGUUCAAUGAAAUGUACACUUUAAGUGGGAAUGUAAACCAGUACAUUGCAAUAGAUGGCAAGAGUAAGCUGUGGCCAAGGUCACAAAAUGGCAACAUGUGGAUUGCUUUGCUCCACAGAUGUUUUAUUUCGCUGGCCUAGCAUUCAUAAUAUGAUCUGACAUUUAAAAACUGGGAUAUGGAACAUCUCUUGAAAAACUGGAAGUUCUGGAAACACUGGGCCAGCAACCCGCAUGGCACAAAUUGGGUGGGGUUUAGAAUCAGAUGCUCCUCCAGAUGGGAAUGGUAGCACCAGACCACUGCAGUCUCACUUGGCCUGCUUCACUUCUUUACCUUAUCUGCCUGGUACCACAGGCACUUGGAUUUGGGAUCGCUGGAUGUUAGUAAGGUCAUAGAUCCGGGCCCUCCAGAGAGAACAAAUUGUUGUUAUAUGUGGGGAGUGCUUUCUAAAAAGGAAGCAGUUGUUUGCUCUCAUUUUGCUAAAGAAAUAAAACAAUAGUCAAUGCC